AUUGGUGUGUAGUCCCGCGCAGUCGCCGGCUCUCCUUUUCCGGACUCUGGGGAUCUCUUGCUGCAACUGACAAGGUAAUUCAUGCCCCGCUUUGGCCCGGGGUCCGAGGCUGUGGUUGCUCAAGGCCACUUAAAAACCAACAAAGCACCAAUUGAAGGCUGUGCAACUUUCAGAUGGCAGGUUGUUCAAAGGAUUUUUUCCUCCAAGCCUCAGAUUAUGAAAGGGACUCAUUCCAGUGCGUUUUUCGAGGAGGAGGGAGAAAACGUUGCCCGACCUCCGAGAGAGCUGUGGGACCAGCACUUUAUUUUACAAGGAACUGCAGAGCUCGGGUUCUAACUCCACGGCCCCGCUCUCUGAGGUGUUCAGGACAGGGCCUCCUCUUUCCCAGCCUUCAGGUCAGCCGGAUCACCAGGGCCUUGCGGGCCAGUUCCCCCUGCCGCGGUUGGGAGGGUCAGUGCAGCGGUCGCCGCGGCCAGAGCGCGCGGAGCUCGGGGGAGGCCGGAUUCCCUAGGUCUGAGCCGACCCUCCCGGCCGCCCGGCCGGGCGGCAGCGACCGCAUCCAUUCCUUUGUAAGUUGCACCGGCCUCAGGAAGUCGAUCUGGGCCCUCCCGGUUCGUUGGCGGUGGGCGUGGGAGACGCAGCCUGCGGAUAGCUCAGGGUCAGGGGAGAGGUGGAGGAAUGCGAAGCUUGUGGGUAGUUCUGCGGUGACGGACAGGGUUGGCGUGGAACCAUUCCCCGCCCCUUUUACCAGCCUUUAUGGGACCGAUGAGACAACUCUUUAACUCUCCUUUGGGUGUUUACCUAAAAUUUAUUGGCUCUGUAAACAGUAUUAAUCACAGUAGUAUUAACCUUCCCUGGAGCGCUUCCGAGUGUAAAUGGCAGUUCUUGGCACUCACCGUUUUCUUUUACUGUGUUUCAAGCAGAGCAGCAAACUCUUGUCCGCUUGGCUUCCUUUUCUACUAUCUCAAUCGUUCCUAGGUUUUGGUUCCUAUAGUAAAUUAAUGAAUAGUGUUUGCAUUACACAGCAUUUCCAUCAUAAUGCACACUGUUGGAUAUAUAUGUGCUAUAUACAUAAAAUAUAGUACAAAAUAAAAAUUAUAUACAUAUAUUCAUUGUAUAAUUCCUAAAAUCUUAAAAAAUUGAAACAUUAGUUUUGUCUUUAAGGCUGUCACCUUAUGUUUAUUUUUUAAACACCUUAUGUUUAUUUCAUACACUCUUGCUUGGUGGUCCAUAUGACAGCCGGAAGCGUUCUGAAGGGAGAGUUAGUGAAUAUCGACUUGACUGGAUUGGUUUCAGUAAGAACAUCUGGCUUUUACAGAAUAUCAUUUGAGGGAAGGGAAAUCUAGGGCAGAGGUAACAAUAAAUUGCAUUUGUAUAGGGCUUGAAGCUUCUAAAGCAACAUCUCAUUCAUUGAUUCUCAGUUUCUCACCUAGCCUUCUGUGAAGAUGGUGUUCCCU